AUUCUCCUGCCUCAGCCUCCCGAGUAGCUGGGACUACAGGCGCCUGCCACCACGCCCGGCUAAUUUUUUGUAUUUUUUAGUAGAGACGGGGUUUGACGGUGUUAGCCAGGAUGGUCUCGAUCUCCUGACCUCAUGAUCUGCCCGCCUCGGCCUCCCAAGGUGCUGGGAUUACAGGCGUGAACCACCGUGCCCGGCCGAACCACUGAAGGUUUUUAAGCAGGAAAGCAGAGCUGUUUUCUGGAUGAGCAAACAGAAAGUAGUGGUUUUCCAAGUACAGUCUGAGACAACCUAUAGGACCAGAAUCUCUGCAGUUGAGGCUCAGGAAUCUGGUAAUCAGCCAGGUAUAGGAACUCUUUUCUGAUUGCAAUGCAGUGAAGAGCAGAAGCACUGUAUUAGAGAAAGAGGCAGUGCAACCAGGUAACGUGACCAGGUGAGAAGUGAUGAGGUACAGAGACAAAGAGAUGCACUUUUGAGUCACUUAGAUGGCACUGAUAGGACUUCCACUACACCCUCGCAUAGACAGUGGCUGAGGUUCAGGAAAUAGAGCUGGGGUUCCUACUUGGAUCCUCUGGCUCUAGAGCUUUACUGCACAUAGCCAUUUAUACCCACAUCUUGAUUUUAAUUAUUUUAUAUCUAUGUUUCUUAGCACUUUUUGCAAAUUUCCACCUUAUCUCAAACUGCCCUCAAGCCUUGUAUUUCUCCUUCGCUUUCAUAAAACCUAGGAAAGAAAUAAGGGACAGCCAAGUAAAACUUUUAAAAGUUUUAGAACAUUUAUUUCUUUGGGGCUGGUUACACAGGCGAGAAAGAAGUAGAUUUGGUUAGGGAGAGAAAACAACAGGCCUUGGGGAGAUACACUGGCUCUCCCCCUCCCUAAACCCUAAGAGGCCUCCAGGAAACCUGAAGACAAUAAUUCCAGAAGCCCAGAGGGUGACCCCAUUUCCUCUCUCCAUGGUUAUUACUGUCAGUCUGGAGCAGUUCAGGAAUUCAGGAAACUAUAAAGAAACCACAACAGCCUCAACAACCCAAACAUCAACAUCAACAACCUCAACAAUAAAACUCCUUAAAAUUCAUCUCCUUCCACCCACUCACAACCGCAGACUCGAAGCUAGGAGGUGGAAGGGACUACAGAAGCUCUGCGUUGCCCAGGAGUUCCUUCUGUCCCGGCUCUGUUCCGUCUCGCCCCGAGGUUCACGCCAUCCUCGGAGCCCCAGCCUUUCACCCAGCGCCUCCAAGCUUUGGACCUUGACUUCUGCAAAACUAGAUGGUCACAGCCAUGAAUGUCUCACAUGAAGUAAAUCAGCUGUUCCAGCCCUAUAACUUCGAGCUGUCCAAGGACAUGAGGCCCUUUUUCGAGGAGUAUUGGGCAACCUCAUUCCCCAUAGCCCUGAUCUACCUGGUUCUCAUCGCUGUGGGGCAGAACUACAUGAAGGAACGCAAGGGCUUCAACCUGCAAGGGCCUCUCAUCCUCUGGUCCUUCUGCCUUGCAAUCUUCAGUAUCCUGGGGGCAGUGAGGAUGUGGGGCAUUAUGGGGACUGUGCUACUUACCGGGGGCCUAAAGCAAACCGUGUGCUUCAUCAACUUCAUCGAUAAUUCCACAGUCAAAUUCUGGUCCUGGGUCUUUCUUCUCAGCAAGGUCAUAGAACUCGGAGACACAGCCUUCAUCAUCCUGCGUAAGCGGCCACUCAUCUUUAUUCACUGGUACCACCACAGCACAGUGCUCGUGUACACAAGCUUUGGAUACAAGAACAAAGUGCCUGCAGGAGGCUGGUUCGUCACCAUGAACUUUGGUGUUCAUGCCAUCAUGUACACCUACUACACUCUGAAGGCUGCCAACGUGAAGCCCCCCAAGAUGCUGCCCAUGCUCAUCACCAGCCUGCAGAUCUUGCAGAUGUUUGUAGGAGCCAUCGUCAGCAUCCUCACGUACAUCUGGAGGCAGGAUCAGGGAUGCCACACCACGAUGGAACACUUAUUCUGGUCCUUCAUCUUGUAUAUGACCUAUUUCAUCCUCUUUGCCCACUUCUUCUGCCAGACCUACAUCAGGCCCAAGGUCAAAGCCAAGACCAAGAGCCAGUGAAGGUUUGGAGAGAACAAUGAAGCUCCAGGCUCUCUCUUCUCCAGGGCACCAAGAGGCUGGGCUUAGUUUUGGGAGAAUGAUUAGGUUGCCUUACCUGCAUGGUUUCCCCAGAGGAUGUGUGCCCCAAGGUGGCUGGAAUUUUUGACAGACAAGAAGGGUGACCUUGGGAUGGGGGUGUGGUCUGUUACUUUAAUGUUUCUGUUUUUAAUGUGAAGGCCAAGCAGGCCCUGGGAUGGGAGUGGGGCGGAGGAGGGUCCUAAGAGCUGAUUAUUUAAUUUCUAUCCAGAAAUCUUUCUUCUUCUUGCUCUGUUUUUUUAAAUUAAAGAUUUCAACAAAA